GCCUUCCCACCCCCCGCCCUUCCACUAUGGCCGCUUCUGUGUGGUGUGGGGAGACGCUGGUCCUCCCCGUCCUCCCAUAGCGCUUAUUGCCUCACCCUCACCCCCUAGGGGCCGGAUCCAAAGGCGCUGCACUCCCCAAGCCUUGGGGCAUCAGCCAGGAAGGUUUCCUACCUCCUAAUUCAGGGGCAGGACUCCUCUUUUCCCCCCACGGGGAAAAGAGGCAGAAACUUAGGGGUUUCCCUCCUUUCUUAGGGUCAGACGCUCUUAGGGUCCACUUCUUCAGGGGCGGAAGCCUCUCCUACCCUUCCCAUAGGGACACAGGCCUUUACCCCACUGUACUUCGGAGCCAACGCCUUUCCCUCAGCACUGCCACCCCAGAGUCAGGACCCAGAGGACUGUGCCUUCGCCCCCAACGCAGGCGCGGCCUUUUGGAGAGGAGGGAGGAGUGGAGAGGACAGGGGCCCUUGCUCUCCCCUCCCCAACUUGUUCCUCUUGCCCCCCAGUCCCUGGCAAUCCAGAGAUCCCGAUAUCUAGGACUGUCCAUCCAUCCACUCCCUGACCUUUUCCCGGCUCCUGGCUGCAGCCAUGGAGUUGCAGAAGGGAAAAGGGGCGGCAGCAGCAGCAGCUGCUUCGGGAGCAGCGGGAGGUGGAGGAGGAGGAGCGGGAGCAGGAGCCCCAGGAGGGGGGAGGCUGCUACUUUCAACCAGUUUGGAUGCCAAGGAUGAGUUAGAGGAGAGAUUGGAAAGGUGUAUGAGCAUUGUGACAUCGAUGACUGCUGGUGUCUCGGAGAGAGAAGCCAAUGAUGCCCUCAAUGCGUAUGUGUGCAAAGGCCUCCCCCAGCAUGAAGAAAUCUGCCUGGGCCUGUUUACUCUCAUCCUCACUGAACCUGCCCAAGCCCAGAAGUGUUACCGGGACUUAGCUCUGGUGAGUCGUGAUGGCAUGAAUAUUGUCCUGAAUAAAAUCAACCAGAUACUUAUGGAGAAGUACCUGAAGCUGCAGGAUACCUGCCGUACUCAGUUGGUGUGGUUGGUACGGGAACUGGUGAAGAGUGGGGUUCUGGGAGCCGAUGGUGUUUGUAUGACGUUUAUGAAGCAGAUUGCAGGUGGAGAUGUUACAGCCAAAAAUAUCUGGUUGGCAGAAAGUGUUCUGGAUAUCCUGACAGAGCAAAGGGAGUGGGUCCUGAAGAGCAGCAUCCUCAUUGCCAUGGCUGUUUACACGUACCUCCGCCUCAUCGUGGACCACCAUGGGACUGCCCAGCUCCAGGCCCUGCGACAGAAGGAAGUAGACUUCUGCAUCUCACUGCUUCGGGAACGGUUCAUGGAAUGUCUGAUGAUUGGUCGGGAUCUCGUAAGACUACUUCAGAAUGUUGCUAGGAUACCAGAAUUUGAACUGCUUUGGAAAGAUAUUAUCCAUAAUCCUCAGGCCUUGAGUCCUCAGUUCACAGGUAUCCUACAGCUUCUUCAGUCAAGAACAUCCCGAAAAUUCCUAGCAUGUCGUCUAACCCCGGACAUGGAGACUAAACUCCUCUUCAUGACAUCCCGGGUGCGAUUUGGUCAACAAAAGCGAUACCAAGAUUGGUUCCAGCGCCAGUACCUGUCAACUCCAGAUAGUCAGUCUCUGCGCUGUGACCUCAUUCGCUACAUCUGUGGGGUAGUCCACCCUUCUAAUGAAGUACUGAGUUCAGAUAUCUUGCCCCGGUGGGCCAUCAUUGGUUGGCUCCUGACAACGUGCACGUCAAAUGUCGCUGCCUCCAAUGCCAAGCUGGCUUUGUUUUAUGACUGGCUGUUCUUUAGUCCAGACAAGGAUAGCAUUAUGAACAUAGAACCAGCCAUCCUGGUCAUGCACCACUCCAUGAAGCCCCACCCAGCCAUCACUGCCACACUCCUGGACUUCAUGUGCCGCAUCAUUCCCAACUUCUAUCCACCAUUGGAGGGCCACGUGCGGCAGGGUGUCUUUUCCUCCCUCAACCACAUUGUGGAGAAACGGGUCUUGGCACACCUAGCUCCCCUGUUUGACAACCCUAAGUUGGAUAAGGAGCUGCGGGCAAUGCUGAGAGAGAAGUUUCCUGAGUUCUGCAGCUCACCCUCCCCACCUGUGGAAGUCAAAAUUGAGGAGCCAGUUUCCAUGGAGAUGGACAACCAUAUGUCGGAUAAGGAUGAGAGUUGCUAUGACAAUGCAGAGGCAGCCUUCAGUGACGAUGAAGAGGAUCUCAACAGCAAAGGAAAGAAGAGGGAGUUUCGCUUCCACCCUAUCAAGGAGACAGUUGUGGAGGAGCCAGUUGAUAUCACCCCUUACCUUGACCAGUUGGAUGAGUCCCUGAGGGACAAAGUACUCCAGCUACAGAAGGGGAGUGAUACGGAGGCCCAGUGUGAGGUCAUGCAGGAAAUUGUGGACCAGGUCCUGGAGGAAGACUUUGACUCGGAGCAGCUGUCUGUCCUUGCUUCCUGCCUACAGGAGCUCUUCAAGGCCCACUUUCGAGGGGAGGUCCUGCCUGAGGAGAUUACUGAGGAGUCCCUGGAGGAGUCUGUAGGAAAGCCUCUGUACCUAAUAUUUAGGAACCUAUGUCAGAUGCAGGAAGACAACAGCAGCUUCUCUCUACUUCUAGACCUUCUCUCCGAGCUAUAUCAGAAGCAGCCCAAGAUUGGCUACCACCUGCUCUACUACCUGAGGGCCAGCAAAGCCGCCGCAGGGAAGAUGAACCUGUACGAGUCAUUUGCCCAGGCUACCCAGCUGGGCGAUCUGCACACCUGCCUGAUGAUGGACAUGAAGGCCUGCCAGGAGGACGAUGUGCGGCUCCUGUGCCACCUCACGCCCUCCAUCUACACAGAGUUUCCAGAUGAAACCUUGAGGAGCGGAGAGCUGCUGAACAUGAUCGUGGCUGUUAUUGACUCUGCACAGCUCCAGGAGCUGGUCUGCCACGUGAUGAUGGGUAACCUGGUUAUGUUUCGAAAAGACUCAGUUCUCAACAUACUCAUUCAGAGCCUAGACUGGGAGACCUUUGAGCAGUAUUGUGCCUGGCAGCUCUUUCUGGCCCACAAUAUUCCCCUGGAGACCAUAAUCCCCAUCCUGCAGCACCUCAAAUACAAGGAGCACCCAGAGGCCCUGUCCUGCCUACUGCUUCAACUCCGAAGAGAAAAGCCCAGCGAGGAGAUGGUGAAGAUGGUGCUGAGCCGGCCCUGCCAUCCUGACGACCAGUUCACCACCAGCAUCCUGCGGCACUGGUGCAUGAAACAUGACGAGCUGCUGGCCGAGCACAUCAAGUCCCUGCUCAUCAAGAACAACAGCCUGCCUCGCAAGAGACAGAGCCUGAGGAGCUCUAGCAGCAAGCUGGCCCAGCUGACUCUGGAGCAGAUCCUGGAGCACUUGGACAAUCUGCGGCUCAACCUGACCAACACCAAGCAGAACUUUUUUAGCCAGACGCCAAUUCUCCAGGCGCUGCAGCAUGUCCAAGCGAGCUGUGACGAAGCCCACAAGAUGAAAUUCAGUGAUCUCUUCUCCCUGGCGGAGGAAUAUGAGGACUCUUCCACCAAGCCACCCAAGAGCCGGCGAAAAGCAGCUCUGUCCAGCCCUCGAAGUCGAAAGAAUGCCACACAGCCCCCCAAUGCCGAAGAAGAGUCGGGCUCCAGCAGUGCUUCAGAAGAGGAAGACACGAAACCGAAGCCUACCAAGCGGAAACGAAAAGGGUCCUCUGCAGUGGGCUCUGACAGUGACUGAGGCCCUGCAUUCCCCAUCCCACCCCCGGCUGGACUGCCCUCUCCUUCUUGGUGAUUCAAAGGUUAAUAGAGGCUGAGGAGAUUGCAGGGGAAACACCCUUGCUGCAUCCCCAAGCUCCCCCGGUGGAAGGAGGAGCUUUCUCCUCUGGCUGAGUUUGAGAAGCUGCCAUGCAGCCCCUAGCCCCUUCCCUCCUCCUGGGGCCUCCAGCCCCUCACACUGCUGUUCCCAGUGAUAUUUGGGAUCUGACUGAAGCCAGAGGCUCUGUAAAAUCAGACCAUAGUGGAAGUCCUCAGCCCCCUGGCCCCUUCCGCAAUCUCCUCCCCCAGUCUCCCAAAGAGCCAUUUCAACAGAGAAGGGAAAUGACAAAGGGGCAGCUGGCCAGAUAAGCUAGGAUGAGAGCAGAGACUCAGUGUGUGGGUGUCCCUUCCUGCUUCCCCUUCAGGUCUUGGUUUGUUCUGAAGGGACGUUUUAUAGUCACUAUCCACAUGCCAGUGUGAAAUGGGCAUCUAUGACGUGGUCAGGGUGUCCAUUCCUAAUCAUGGGGCAGAUGCCACAAGCAUUCAGAAAGGAGUCUGAAAGGGUGGCCACAGCCCCACGUGGUGUGCCCUGGAGGCUUAGGUUGGUCUGAGGUUGGCACCUCAAUCUACACCAGAGCCCAGGGAGUCCCAGAGGCAAGUUUCACAGAAUUGUCAAAUGAUCCCAUUUCCUUGAGUCUGUUUUUUUUUUUGUUUUUUUUUGUUUUUUUUUUGGCAGAGAUAAUCGUGUCUUAAAAGUUGUUUUUAAAUGACAAUAAAACAAGCCAGAAUGUCUUUUGUGCUGGAGUGUCUGCUGGCAUUUGCCCCGUGCAUGUAUAGCUUGGUCUUGAUUUGAUUGGCACCCCUACUUGUAACCGCAGAACAUCCCCCUUUCCCUUCCUGUUCUGCCCCCACUUUUGUCUAGAGCAGAAGGGACUUGGCUUUGGCCACUACCCAUCCUUCCUGCUGCCACUGGAGGUGGGAGCCAGGCACUGAUCUGUCUAUGCAGAACCAUCCCCCGUAGGAUGAGGCCUGUCCUUACUCAUUUCUCAAGAAACAAGAUGCUUCCAAAAGGUCUGUCAUCCUCCAGUUGAAGUCUGUGUGCCUACCAAGAAUGGCCGGAGGACUCGCUGCUUGACGGGAGGGAUGCUCCAGCUUGGUCUCCAGGGACAACUGUACCUGGAGAUAAAGUCUGGAUACCAGGGAGGGACAGAGAUGCUCUUCCUUCCACAGUGUGGCCACUUGCUGGGCCAUGUGAACCAGCAGAGGAGAGUUCCUUGGCUAUGCUGUUGUUCCCCCGCUGUCCAGGGAGAAUGGAGGUGGACUGAGGAGUGAAGUUUGGGCGAACUGCACAGAGCUGCUCCUCUUCACCCCGAAAAUUUGUCUUUUUACAGAAUCCAGGUUCUCCCCUCCCUCAUCACUGCUGUUGCUUCCUUUGAAAGUCUAAACCACUGGAGGCUUCUUUUUCCUUCCUCUCUCCUUCCCCAGUUUCCUCUGUCCCAAUUAAAACCAGGAUGGAGAGCA